GUCUUCCUCCCCCAGGGUUGUGGCCACGCGCAGCGGCGGCGGUUGUUCCGCUUCCCCUCCGGCCCGGGCCGUCGCCAUUGCCGAAGGCUCCCUCCCCUCCCCUCCCUGGCGUGCGCAGGACUCCGCCGCCGCUGGGCCUAGCGGUAGCAGCGGCUGCUCCAGCGCGGCGUCUCUUCCCGCCCCGCUUCCCCUUCCCUCCCCUCCCCUCCCCGCACCGCGCGCUAGCCCGGGGCGGCUCCGCAGCCCGCCGGGAGCUCUGACCGAGGCGCCUCGCUGGGGCGGGGACCUUGCCUUGCCCGGGGCCAUUUCAUAAUUCUGAAUCAUGUCUGAUAACGGAGAACUGGAAGAUAAGCCUCCAGCACCUCCUGUGCGAAUGAGCAGCACCAUCUUUAGCACUGGAGGCAAAGACCCUUUGUCAGCCAAUCACAGUUUGAAACCUUUGCCCUCUGUUCCAGAAGAGAAAAAGCCCAGGCAUAAAAUCAUCUCCAUAUUCUCAGGCACAGAGAAAGGAAGUAAAAAGAAAGAAAAGGAACGGCCAGAAAUUUCUCCUCCAUCUGAUUUUGAGCACACCAUCCAUGUUGGCUUUGAUGCUGUUACUGGAGAAUUCACUGGCAUGCCAGAACAGUGGGCUCGAUUACUACAGACCUCCAAUAUCACCAAACUAGAGCAAAAGAAGAAUCCUCAGGCUGUGCUGGAUGUCCUAAAGUUCUACGACUCCAACACAGUGAAGCAGAAAUAUCUGAGCUUUACUCCUCCUGAGAAAGAUGGCUUUCCUUCUGGAACACCAGCACUGAAUGCCAAGGGAACAGAAGCACCCGCAGUAGUGACAGAGGAGGAGGAUGAUGAUGAAGAGACUGCUCCUCCCGUUAUUGCCCCGCGACCGGAUCAUACGAAAUCAAUUUACACACGGUCUGUAAUUGACCCUGUUCCUGCACCAGUUGGUGAUUCACAUGUUGAUGGUGCUGCCAAGUCUUUAGACAAACAGAAAAAGAAGACUAAGAUGACAGAUGAAGAGAUUAUGGAGAAAUUAAGAACUAUCGUGAGCAUAGGUGACCCUAAGAAAAAAUAUACAAGAUAUGAAAAAAUUGGACAAGGGGCUUCUGGUACAGUUUUCACUGCUACUGACGUUGCACUGGGACAGGAGGUUGCUAUCAAACAAAUUAAUUUACAGAAACAGCCAAAGAAGGAACUGAUCAUUAACGAGAUUCUGGUGAUGAAAGAAUUGAAAAAUCCCAACAUCGUUAACUUUUUGGACAGUUACCUGGUAGGAGAUGAAUUGUUUGUGGUCAUGGAAUACCUUGCUGGGGGGUCACUCACUGAUGUGGUAACAGAAACGUGCAUGGAUGAAGCACAGAUUGCUGCUGUAUGCAGAGAGUGUUUACAGGCAUUGGAGUUUUUACAUGCUAAUCAAGUGAUCCACAGAGACAUCAAAAGUGACAAUGUACUUUUGGGAAUGGAAGGAUCUGUUAAGCUCACUGACUUUGGUUUCUGUGCCCAGAUCACCCCUGAGCAGAGCAAACGCAGUACCAUGGUCGGAACGCCAUACUGGAUGGCACCAGAGGUGGUUACACGGAAAGCUUAUGGCCCUAAAGUCGACAUAUGGUCUCUGGGUAUCAUGGCUAUUGAGAUGGUAGAAGGAGAGCCUCCAUACCUCAAUGAAAAUCCCUUGAGGGCCUUGUACCUAAUAGCAACUAAUGGAACCCCAGAACUUCAGAAUCCAGAGAAACUUUCCCCAAUAUUUCGGGAUUUCUUAAAUCGAUGUUUGGAAAUGGAUGUGGAAAAAAGGGGUUCAGCCAAAGAAUUAUUACAGCAUCCUUUCCUGAAACUGGCCAAACCGUUAUCUAGCUUGACACCACUGAUCAUGGCAGCUAAAGAAGCAAUGAAGAGUAACCGUUAACAUCACUGCUGUGGCCUCAUACUCUUUUUUCCAUUUUCUACAAGAAGCCUUUUAGUAUAUGAAAAUUAUUACUCUUUUUGGGGUUUAAAGAAAUGGUCUGCAUAACCUGAAUGAAAGAAGCAAAUGACUAUUCUCUGAAGACAACCAAGAGAAAAUUGCAAAAAGACAAGUAUGACUUUUAUAUGAACCCCUUCUUUAGGGUCCAGAAGGAAUUGUGGACUGAAUCACUAGCCUUAGGUCUUUCAGCAAACAGCCUAUCAGGGCCAUUUAUCAUGUGUGAGAUUUGCAUUUUACUUUGCUGACUUUGUUGUAAUAGAUCCCAUUCAUUGUCCCCUUUGGGGUAUUUCCAAUACUUGAAUGGCAGAUUGGAGUUUUUCAGAGUAUGUGUUUCAUCUGCUAGUCUUUCUCUCCUUCAUAGCUUUUCUUUUCCUGGACUUGCUCCUUUUGAGUUGCUUUUGCGUUUCUCAUGCCUAGGCAAGUGUAAUAGAAAUUAUGUAGCUCCUUAUGUUGGCAAAGGAGCUCUAUAUAGUUUCACUUUGUAUAAAAGUUAGGACCAGCUGUUGUUACAUGUAAUAUUUUAGUUCAGAACUUGACCUGAAGGAAGGGAAGAAAAGUAUGUGAUUUUUACCUUUUUUAACAAAUGUGAAAAAGUCAGUUUUAGAAAUUUCGUGGUAGUAAGUUCGGCAUUUGUUACAUGUAUAGAGAGAAGACUAAUAAUCUCUAUUUAUAACUAAAUCAUUGAGAUAGAAAAAGAUUCCCAUUGACUGUAGACUUCUUCCCAUUUUGUCUUCCCUUCUGCCUGUUUCCCCUUCAGGCUUGGCUCUAGGAACCAAAGUGAUUUGUUGUUGUUCCAACCUGGGCUUUGUGACUUUGGUUAGUGCCACUACCUUCUUCCCUCCUUUCCCCCUUCAAUUUGGAAAUAAAUUUCUGUAUAUGUUGCAAUUUUAGGUUUAGGUUUGUUCUUUUUCUUUUUCAUUAAUCCUCUCUCACCUCACAGAUACCCCCUCCCAUGGCAAAUAAUAUAAUAACCAGUGAAUUUUCAGGAAUUUAAAAAUUAGCUUUUUUCCACUUAAAGGAGAAAAAUAUUUGGGACUAGCAGCAGAGGCAGUAAGAGAUGUGAACCUUGGUGAGCUCUGAUACAGUGAGAAGAGAUUAUACUCAUGAAAGAGAAUGUUAGUGUUACAGAGAAGCAGCCGAUAGCAAAUCGACUGUAGAGACUUGGCGGCGGUGGCAUUGCCCCAGGUCGUCAGCAGUGUGGUAUUAUCUAUGAGAACUUGAGCGACAGAGUAUUUCUUGAUGAAUUUAUAGAUCAUUUGAGAUGUUGAGUUACUUUAGUUUAGUUUUGUUUUGUUUUUUCAAAUAAGUAGAGACUAUUGUAAAAAACGAGAAAGGAAAAUGAAAUGUGCGUGUUGAUAGCAAUAAUUUGUUUCUUUUAAAGAUUCUAAAAGGUCUGAGACCUGUAGCAUUAAUUAUUUGAGUGCCCUCCCUUCUCCCCUCCCCUCCCUUUUCUCUUCUCUUUUUUCCUCUCCUCUUCUUCUCCUUUAUUCAUUGUUUUGCUUUUGGAGUGGGUGUUGUUCAAGUAUCUGUGGUUUGGUUCUGGCAUUUUGUUCCCACCAUCCCCUUCCCCCAUUAACUUCCCCCCUGCUUGCCAUCCUGCAGUAGUAUAAAUCAUGAAUAAAAAAUAAUUUUGCUGUUGUAGUAUACAUUGGAGAAACUGGCAGGUUUUAUUUCCAUUAUUUUAUUUCCACUAUAUCUAUGAUAAGAUGCAAUUAUAAGGAGAGAAGUGACUGUUUUUUAUUGAUAAGGCAAGAUUUUCAGAAAAAUGAGUAAAAUAAUUAAUGAAACAUAUUUAGAGCACUUAAUGGUCUCUGUUUUCAAUAUAAUUCUUGAUUUCAUUUUUCUCUGGAAUAUAUUGGCCUUCUACAGCUAUUACUGAAUUAUAGAAACUGGUUUAUUUCUGGCAGAAAGCUGCAGUGCCACCUGAGUUCCAAAUUUUACCAUUCUUUGUAAACAGUUGGAUGGAUUAUGAUAAAGAAGAUGCUACCAAUGAAAUAGAAAACCAACGAGAUGAGAAGACUGUGAUCCUCAUGUACUCAGAGGCACUUCCCUCCUAAGUCAAAGACCAUCCUCACUGACUAUGUGCCAACGCCUCGUUUCAGGCUUGUGACUCAACAAAGGGCUUUUCCAUUGAUAGAAGCAGUUUGGGAUUUGUAGUUGCGACUUCUUCGAUAGUUACCUGCACGUCCAUUGCUGGCAACUGACUUGUCAUUAAAACCUGGCUCUUUGGUUAAGGGAGCUACGCUGUGGUUUAUUCUUAAGUUACGUGGAUAAACUAACCUCUAACAGAAAUAUACUUUGGUUAAUUUUGAAAUGUGUCAUUUUUAAACAAUCUUAAAAGUAAUACAGAAUUGUGAUUUAUUAAUUUUAAAACAUUCAGAACUUGUUGAAAGAAAAAUUAUAUCUGAAUCAAGAUUCAUGUUUUUUAUUUUUAUUUUUUUUGAUACAGAGUCUCACUCUGUCACUCAGGCUGGAGUGCAGUGACAUGAUCUCAGCUCACUGCAACCUCCGCUUCCUGGGUUCAAGCAAUUCUCAUGCCUCAGCCUCCUGAGUAGCUGAGACCACAGGCACCCGCCACCACACCCAGCUAUUUUUUUGUAUUUUUAGUAGAGACAGAGUCUCACCACAUUGCCCAGGCUGGUCUCCAACUCCUGAGCUCAGGCAGUCUGCCCACCUUGGCCUCCCAAAGUGCUGCAGUUACAGGCGUGAGCCACUGCACCUGGCCUCAUGUUUUUUAAAUAAUUGCCUUUUAUAUUUACCCUUUUUGUCAUCACUUUAGAAUGAAAAUUCCCAUUUAAAUCUGAAAGUUACCUUAAUAGUCCUCUUGUGUUAUUAGGACAGUAUUAUUAUAGUACUUAUUUAUUUUAUUUUAGAUUUAAAGUUAUCUUCUCUUUUUCUUUUUUCUUCUGCUGCUUUUAGGGACAAUUAAAACUGGGAAACUAUGAAACAUGGAACAUUUUAUCCUACCUGAAAGUAAACGAGUAAUUGUGAAGCAUAAGACACUGAGGCUAAUACAACUCUGUCUUCAUGUGUUGACUGCCUGGCACAUAGUAUUCAUUCUCUUCCCUUUAACAUAGAAGUGUCCAGCUGCGUACAGUCUAGUAACCAGCAACUGUAAACGAACCUGUGCCUCUAACAAGCGAUUCUAAACCACCUAUGAGUAUUUCUUUUAGGGCUCACUUAAAUACAUGUUUGUAUAUACUGUAUUCUAGCCAGAAUAAUUUUAGAUCUGAUCAGGUAGUAGCUAAAAUUAGAAAAAAACAAAAUAGAUGCUUAAAGAAUUUGCAUCCAUUUUUGAGUCUAAAUCUUUUAAAAUAUACUGAGAUCCACAUCUAGUGAAAUGUCAGUGUCAAAAUAUUAUAGAUUAUAGCUAAAAUCCAGAUUAAUACUCAUUUGGGGUUUUUUAUAGUGGAACUUCAUAGUAAUACAAAAAGCAGAUUGUCUUCCUGUCUCCGCUGCUCCCACAGUAGGUAUUGAAACUGGUAAAAUCAGUUUUUUGAUAGUGUGUGUAUAUAAGAAAAAAUAGAUACACACAUUCUUUUUUCUCAGUCAACACAUUGAUUGAACACUCUGGCAAAGAUGCUGUGGUGGAUGAGGUUGGAGUUCGAAAGAAGAAGCAAGCGCUGGCCUGGCCUUGAAAGAACCGAAGUCUUUCCCAUUCACUUCUCUAGAAAGCUGCCAAGACAGAGGCAGAAAGAAAUGGAUGAUAGUUCUGUCAAGCACACUUCUGUUCUCUUAGAACUUAGAAGUGUUUCUAAGAGAACAGAAGUAAUAAGAGAAACAGUUACGUGUGGAAUUCAACAUCUUUGGUUGGAACGCAUUGGCUUUUUUUUUCUUGUUUUGAUAGAAAUGGAAUUAAGCAAAAGUAGUUUUUGUCUUUUCUGUUGUCUUCAAAUUUUAUGCCUUUUAUUUUUAAUUUAAUCCCGUUCAAUUAUUUAAUUGUUAUACAUUGACAUUAACUGCUGUAUUUUGACUUUGUUCAAUAAUUUUGUUCUUUCAGGGCUAGAAAUAAACUUUUUAAAAAAAGUGUGCAUUUUUCCCUUUCCUAAACUUUUAUUCUUUCUUUUGAUCAGCGUAAAAGAAUAUUUUAAUGUCUUUUGAUAGCAUAAAAGAAUAUUUAAAUGUCUUAAUAGGUUUUCAAAGAACAUUUAGUAUUUUUAGUGAUAAAUGUUUUAAACCUUUUAA